GACCUCUCCUCUCCCAGCCAGUCGUGGCUGGCCUUUCAAAGUGUGCAGUUGUCUCCUCCCUGUCCAGCCCCAUCGUCGCCCAGGACCAGCUGGGCCGCGGUCUGACCUGAGGCUGCUGCUCAGCGCCGGGGCGCUGGCGCUCUCCAUUCGAGCACCUUCCAGCAUACCGCUCGGCUCCGGGAGCCGCUCUGCAAAGUUGGGCAGCUCAGAGCGCAAGCUUUGCCUCUCGACUUCUCCCUCCUUGGGUCCCCGGCGCCCCCGCCUCCCACGAUCCCUUUCACUAGGAGCAGCCAGUCCCAGCGGGCUGGCAACUUGCACCCCUUCCUAGUCAUCCUCCCUGAAACGCGACCAUGCUGUUAAGGGGCGUCCUCCUGGCGUUGCAAGCCCUGCAGCUCGCCGGUGCCCUCGACCUGCCCGCUGGGUCCUGUGCCUUUGAAGAGAGCACUUGCGGCUUUGACUCCGUGUUGGCCUCUCUGCCGUGGAUUUUAAAUGAGGAAGGCCAUUACAUUUAUGUGGAUACCUCCUUUGGCAAGCAGGGGGAGAAAGCUGUGCUGCUAAGUCCUGACUUACAGGCUGAGGAAUGGAGCUGCCUCCGUUUGGUCUACCAGAUAACCACAUCUUCGGAGUCUCUGUCAGAUCCCAGCCAGCUGAACCUCUACAUGAGAUUUGAAGAUGAAAGCUUUGAUCGCUUGCUUUGGUCAGCUAAGGAACCUUCAGACAGCUGGCUCAUAGCCAGCUUGGAUUUGCAAAACAGUUCCAAGAAAUUCAAGAUUUUAAUAGAAGGUGUACUAGGACAGGGAAACACAGCCAGCAUCGCACUAUUUGAAAUCAAGAUGACAACCGGCUACUGUAUUGAAUGUGACUUUGAAGAAAAUCAUCUCUGUGGCUUUGUGAACCGCUGGAAUCCCAAUGUGAACUGGUUUGUUGGAGGAGGAAGUAUUCGGAAUGUCCACUCCAUUCUCCCACAGGAUCACACCUUCAAGAGUGAACUGGGCCACUACAUGUACGUGGACUCAGUUUAUGUGAAGCACUUCCAGGAGGUGGCACAGCUCAUCUCCCCGUUGACCACGGCCCCCAUGGCUGGCUGCCUGUCAUUUUAUUACCAGAUCCAGCAGGGGAAUGACAAUGUCUUUUCCCUUUACACUCGGGAUGUGGCUGGCCUUUACGAGGAAAUCUGGAAAGCAGACAGGCCAGGGAAUGCUGCCUGGAACCUUGCGGAGGUCGAGUUCAGUGCUCCUUACCCCAUGGAGGUUAUUUUUGAAGUUGCUUUCAAUGGUCCCAAGGGAGGUUAUGUUGCCCUGGAUGAUAUUUCAUUCUCUCCUGUUCACUGCCAGAAUCAGACAGAACUUCUGUUCAGUGCCGUGGAAGCCAGCUGCAAUUUUGAGCAAGAUCUCUGCAACUUUUACCAAGAUGAAGGUCCAGGUUGGACCCGAGUGAAAGUAAAACCAAACAUGUAUCGGGCUGGAGACCACACUACAGGCUUAGGGUAUUACCUGCUAGCCAACACAAAGUUCACAUCUCAGCCUGGCUACAUUGGAAGGCUCUAUGGGCCCUCCCUACCAGGAAACUUGCAGUAUUGUCUGCGUUUUCAUUAUGCCAUCUAUGGAUUUUUAAAAAUGAGUGACACCCUAGCAGUUUACAUCUUUGAAGAGAACCAUGUGGUUCAAGAGAAGAUCUGGUCUGUGUUGGAGUCCCCAAGGGGUGUUUGGAUGCAAGCUGAAAUCACCUUUAAGAAGCCCAUGCCUACCAAGGUGGUUUUCAUGAGCCUAUGCAAAAGUUUCUGGGACUGUGGGCUUGUAGCCCUGGAUGACAUUACAAUACAAUUGGGAAGCUGCUCAUCUUCAGAGAAACUUCCACCUCCACCUGGAGAGUGUACUUUCGAGCAAGAUGAAUGUACAUUUACUCAGGAGAAAAGAAACCGGAGCAGCUGGCACAGGAGGAGGGGAGAAACUCCCACUUCCUACACAGGACCAAAGGGAGAUCACACUACUGGGGUCUGGCAGCUUAAAGUCCAAGAUCAAGAUGUCGGUAGGGUUGGUUCCUUCUGAAAUUUCUCUCCUUGGCUUGCAGAUGGCUGCCUUCUUGCUUCACAUGGCCUUUCCUCUGUGCCAGUGCACCCCCGAUAUGUAUCUUCUUGUAAGUUCACCAGUCAUAAUGAAUUACAGCCCACCCUAACAAUCCCAUUGUGACUUAAUUACCUCCUAAAAGGUUCUAUCUCCAAAUACAGUCACAUUCUAGUACGUGGGUUAGGGCUUCAACAUACCUCUUUGGAGAAGACACAAUUGAACCCACUCCCAGGAUUUAGGGCAAUGGGUUGAACAUUGAAGGAACAGGGUAAACUCUUAAGUUAAAUGGCUGACAACCAAGCCCUGUCCUGCUCCUCAUGUCAUUAUGCUAAAAUAAUGUUAUAGUCUGAGCUUGCUUGACUAGUAGACCAUGUCCUACCUUCUCCUCAUAAAUACACAGUCUAUGAAAAUCUAACAAAAGCACAUAUAGUAGAUAUUAAAUUGCUCCUAAUUCUACUCCUGUAUUUACAUUAUUUCUGGGUUAUGUGGACACACUUUAGCUAACAUAGUAUUGCUUUGUCUAAAGAAAAUAAUUUGGUUGUGUUUGCUUUGUCUUCUUAAAAACUUUGAAAGAUGCUUCAGCUGCCUCGGGUUAUACUUCAUAGCAAAAAUAGAGUGCAUGUUAUUAUAUGAAUAUAUUGUGGAAAAUUUUGAAUGCACAAACUUAGUGUGUUCAACAUUUAUUUUGAGUGAAUAUUUGACAUAUUAAAUAAAACUCUCUGGUGCACAACACAGAAAA